AGUGCCGGCGCUGCAAGGAAGUUUCCAGAGCUUUCGAGGAAGGUUUCUUCAACUCAAAUUCAUCCGCCUGAUAAUUUUCUUAUAUUUUCCUAAAGAAGGAAGAGAAGCGCAUAGAGGAGAAGGGAAAUAAUUUUUUAGGAGCCUUUCUUACGGCUAUGAGGAAUUUGGGGCUCAGUUGAAAAGCCUAAACUGCCUCUCGGGAGGUUGGGCGCGGCGAACUACUUUCAGCGGCGCACGGAGACGGCGUCUACGUGAGGGGUCAAAAUGCAGAUCUUCGUGAAAACCCUUACCGGCAAGACCAUCACCCUUGAGGUGGAGCCCAGUGACACCAUCGAAAAUGUGAAGGCCAAGAUCCAGGAUAAGGAAGGCAUUCCCCCCGACCAGCAGAGGCUCAUCUUUGCAGGCAAGCAGCUGGAAGAUGGCCGUACUCUUUCUGACUACAACAUCCAGAAGGAGUCGACCCUGCACCUGGUCCUGCGUCUGAGAGGUGGUAUGCAGAUCUUCGUGAAGACCCUGACCGGCAAGACCAUCACCCUGGAAGUGGAGCCCAGUGACACCAUCGAAAAUGUGAAGGCCAAGAUCCAGGAUAAAGAAGGCAUCCCUCCCGACCAGCAGAGGCUCAUCUUUGCAGGCAAGCAGCUGGAAGAUGGCCGCACUCUUUCUGACUACAACAUCCAGAAGGAGUCGACCCUGCACCUGGUCCUGCGUCUGAGAGGUGGUAUGCAGAUCUUCGUGAAGACCCUGACCGGCAAGACCAUCACUCUGGAGGUGGAGCCCAGUGACACCAUCGAAAAUGUGAAGGCCAAGAUCCAAGAUAAAGAAGGCAUCCCCCCCGACCAGCAGAGGCUCAUCUUUGCAGGCAAGCAGCUGGAAGAUGGCCGCACUCUUUCUGACUACAACAUCCAGAAAGAGUCGACCCUGCACCUGGUCCUGCGCCUGAGGGGUGGCUGUUAAUUCUUCAGUCAUGGCAUUCGCAGUGCCCAGUGAUGGCAUUACUCUGCACUAUAGCCAUUUGCCCCAACUUAAGUUUAGAAAUUACAAGUUUCAGUAAUAGCUGAACCUGUUCAAAAUGUUAAUAAAGGUUUCGUUGCAUGGUA